CCAAGCUGGGUAGGGUGGGCAGAAGAGAGCCUGCACCAGGCCCUGGGGGCAGGCAAGGAGAAGGCCGUCAUGCUGUCUGCUGGCUGGCUCACUCAGUGCCAGGCAGUCGCUCCCUGUCCCCGUGGUCCACCCCUCCCUGUGAAGGGCUCAGCCGGCACAGCCCCAGCUCUCACGAAAGGCCAGGCUCUCUAAUCCUGAGCUUACAGACAGCUGGCAGUGGCCACGGGACAAUGAGUCCCCCGACUAUAAAAAACCACAUUACGGAAGGAGUGGAGCCGGCCCCGCAUUCCAUGCGGCGUCUGCGGAGCGUCACUCACCCCGAAGACACGGUCAACCGGGCAAGGCCUGGAGCACAGCCCACCGCCAGCCUCGGGCUCCCACGUGCCCACGCGACACCCUCGCCAGCCACCCCCAUCAUCCAUGCCAGCAGAGCUGACAUCAGUGGCCCUGGAGGAAGAUGCCCAUCUCCAAUGCUGGUCUGCCAAGGUCUUGGGCCAUGGCCUCCCAGGACACCGCACGACUAGGCUCUCGCUGGGCCUCCCUGGGUUCAUGCUCCACCCCCGCUCCCACCCAGCCCCCCCCGGUCUUGGGAAUGCUCAAAGCUCCCUCUGCACACCAGGUCUGCCUGCCAUCUCCACUCAGGAGGCUGCCGUCCCCACCCUCCACACCCCUACAUCUCCACUCAGGAGGCUGCCGUCCCCACCCUCCACACCCCUACAUCUCCACUCAGGAGGCUGCCGUCCCCACCCUCCACACCCCUACAUCUCCACUCAGGAGGCUGCCGUCCCCACCCUCCACACCCCUACAUCUCCACUCAGGAGGCUGCCACCCCCACCCUCCACACCCCUGGCCACCUAGAACACCCCAGACCUUUCCAGACUCAGGCCACAUAACGACACCUUUCAUGAUGCUUUUCUUGGCCUCUGGCCCCCUUCAGUCCCCUGACCCCGACAGCCCCUCUGUGGUGCUCUCACGGACGCCUCCUCUGGGGUUCAGCCCCACCUGCUGCCGUCCCGGCUGCCAGGCUGAGCACCUUGCCGGCAGGGAGCACAAGCCGUCUGUGGUCUCAGUGUCCACCCAAGCGCCCAUAACCAGGAGACCCCCAGUGCUCGGCCUUGGGUGGAAAGACAUAGGUGAGAGGCUGCUGACCGCCCCCCUGCCCCUUCCCCAAGACAGGGUGCGCAUGUUUCCUGUUUGCCUGUGUGUUUGGGGAAAGGGGGGAGAACAGGGCCUGCCCCAUUUUGCUAUAUCACACAGGUGUGACUGCAGCAAAGCCGGCCACUCUGUUUCCCCUAUCCCUGCCCUCAGAGGCCGCUCCUUCUCCAGAGGCUGGUCCACUCCCUCCCUGGAAUCGAAGCCAGCCAGUGAUGGCUCUGGCAUAAAGUGGCAUGAGGGAUGCUCUCCCAGCCCUGCCCCAAGACCGUCAGAGGCCUGGCAGCUUCUGCUCUCUUGGAACCUAUUGAGAAGCCCAAGGUGUCCUAUCGGAGGGUGAGGUUCCUGGAGGGAAACUGAGGCAACCCAGCCAACAGCCGGCACAGUGCUUUCCUGGGCCUUUGGGCCCCACCAUAGCCAAAUGCCACUGCCCGAGGGACCCCAGGCAGCACCUCAUGGGGCAGAGAUGAGCUGUCCUCACUGAGCCCCGUCCAGAUCCCUGGCCCACAGAAUUGCCAGCCAGGGAACAGCCGCCAGCCGCUAGGUGUGGCAGGGUAAAUAGGAGUUAGCUCAGCUGUUAGAGGGUAAGCGGUGGAGGGGGGUGAAAAGGGCACGUCAGACAUCUUUGAGCACAAACGGGUGUCCCAAAGGGCUGUAUAGGAGCCCUGUUGUGGGGGAUAGGAGGCGUGAGGGUAAGAGGAAAGAGCAUGGAAGACGCAGAGAAGCAGGACAGAGUCAGCAGAACACAAGCAGAAGGCCAGGAGCUGCGGGGCUCAGGGCGGCGCCAACUCUGGACAGAGGCUGGGGUUGCUGAGCGGCAGGCAAACCUCACCCACGUUACAGACGCACCUGCUUCCUGAGAAACACGUCUCCAGUGAAAAAGCUGUUGCACUAACUCCAGGACUCACCGGCUUGAGAAAGAAAAUGCUCCUCCACGCAGACAUUUAAUGAGCCAAUUAGAUCUAAGAUGGUUUCCAUCUGAAUAUUCUUGAGUGCCCUCGUGGCUGCCCCUUGAUGUCAGAAUCUUAAGUGCUCAUAAUCCCAGCUCCUCAGAGAACAAACAUCGGGGUGACCAGGGUGUCCUGGAUGGCUCAUGCCAGGUAGGCAUGGGCAGGACUGAGAAGUCUUGAUAACAUGACCCUCAGCCCUCUCCAUCCCCCAAGGUGGCAGCUUCUUGUACACUUGGGAGUGGCCCCACCUAGUGGGUCUCGGGUGGAGGAAGGCCUGGAGCCUGGCAGUGGGUGUUGGCUCCCACCCCUCCUCUGCCCUCCUGAAGCAGCCCCAGUCCAGGGGCACCACUCUAGAAGGCCCCCCCUUCCCGGGCCGGCCCUCCUCCCCUUGUCCAUCACCACCUUGUUAACAUUCCUGCAAUCCACAGGGUUCCCAUCCCCCAACCAGGCAGCUGCUGCCUGGGGCAGCCUCGCCCUCCAUCUUCUGGACCUCAAUCAGAACCUUCUCUGGCCCCUGCCAGCCUCUUCCUCCAAGCUCAUCUGCACCCCGGGGUCAACAUUAGCAUAUAAAACACUCCCCAUGCUCAAGCACCUUCAAUGGCUCCCUGCUGCUCCGAGACAAUGGUGCAAACAAACACUGGUCCAAUUAGCCAGCUCUCUACAACCCAGCCCUGUCUCCUCCUCCUCCUCCACCCUCACGCCUCCUAUCCCCCCCAACAGGGCUCCUACACAGCCCUUCGGGACACCCAUUCGUGCUCAAAGAUGUCUGAAGUGCCCUUUUCACCCCCCUCCACCCCUUACCCUCUGACAGCUGAGCUAACUCCUAUUCACCCUGCAGAAGUCCCCUGAGGCUCGCCCCUCCAGAGAGCUUCCCCGCAGUGCCCCCAGCCUGGGGUCUGUGCCCCUCCUGGCUCCCCUCGCACCCUCUGAGGACUGAAAAUGCCUCACUCAGUCUCACGCAGCCUCUGAGGCCGGACCGUCUGAUCCCUAGGCCCAGCGCCCGGCAAUGAGAAACUGCUGAAGGCGCUCCCUGCUGCCUGACAGAGGCCAGGGUUCCAGCCAGCUCUGUCCAGGCUGCCCCCGCAGGCUGCAGUGGCCAAAGGUGGCCGGCAGGGGGCUCUCCAGAGCUGGGCAGAUGCCGCGUUCAUGUAGCAAGAGCCUCCUAGUUCAGGUUUUCAUUCUUUACUCUUCUUUUUUUGAGACAGAGCCUGGCUCUGUUGCCUUGGCUGGACUGCAAUGGCGGGAUCUCAGCUCACUGCAACCUCCAACUCCCAGGUUCAAGUGAUUUUCCCACCUCAGCCUCUGGAGUAGCUGGGAUUACAGGCACCUGCUACCACACCUGCCUAAUUUUUGUAUUUUUAGUAGAGAUGGGGUUUCACCAUGUUGACCAGGCUGAUCUCGAACUCCUGACCUCAGGUGAUCCUCCCACCUCCGCCUCCCAAAGUGCUGGGAUUACAGACAUGAGCCACUGUGCCUGGCCACAUUCUUAAUCAUUUUUAAAAGUCAAAAUGAGUUUCAAAUGCUCCGGGCGGCCCCCAGAGGCUGGGCAAAGAGGCAGAUAUGGUCCUUGGACUGGACCCAGCUGGAGAGAGCAGGUAAGGGGGGAAAAAGGGGGCACCUCCAAAAGCUUCCAUUCACCCUCAAGGCCCAGCUCAAACGUCCCCCUGCGCCUCCAAAGCCCUCCCUUCCUAGGCUCUGGGUGGGCUCACCCUCUCUGGGGCCCACCACCGUCUGUGCUGCAAGCUGAGCCUGUCCCAGGGCGAGUGGCCCUCUCUGCAUCACUCUCCACCACGCACAGUCCAUCCCCGAAGGCGGGGCCCAGUCACUUGCCCGUGUGUGAGGCUGGAGCCUGCAGACCUGAGCUGUCCACAGACCGUCGCCUGCCAUGUGCCAAGUGCGCUCGGGCCAAGCUCCAGGAGUCCACACUACAGGCCCGUGACCAACAGAGACGGGGAAUUGGGCCACACUGGGGACCCGGGGGUUGCUGUCACCAAGCCACCUCCUGUCCCAUUCUGAACAGGCAGCUGUCCACAGAGAGACCUCUGCCCCCCAGGCACCAAGACCAGCCAGGCCUGUCUCCACCCGACCCCCACCAGGGCCCCCGUGAUGCACAGCCACGCCCAGUGUCUCAGGAUGAGUGAGGCGCAGCCAUCGCCUUGGGCCAGGGUCACCCUCUCUGCUCUCUGCAGAGCUGGCUGUGGCGGGGCCAAGUGAGGCGGUUCUGGGGAUCGGGGGCCAGGCUAGGACCUGUCCCUGGGGAAGGAGGGAAUGUGGAUUUCCUACACCCAAGAACUUCCAGGGCCUUCCCACGACUCCAGCCCAGCUGUGACCUCCAGACUGAAUGUGACGACACCCACAGACUUAUUGGGAUUCAGAUUCUGGAUAUUUCUCCGUCCCAGUGGCCCCAGUUGUCGGCCAAAUGGUGGCCCACAAAAUGUGUUCACAUACCAGGGCCUGUGAACAGGAGCCUCUGCGGAUGGAAUUGAUGGUCUCGGGAUGGGGUCACCCUGGGUCAUCCAGGUGGGCCCUAAGUCCACAGACUGCAAGAGACUGAAGAGGAGGCUCACGCAGGAGCCAGCAGGCGCAGGGACUGGAGUGGCACAGCCACGAGCCGAGGCCGCCGGGGCCACCAGCGGCUGGAAGGGGCAGGAAGGACCUUCCCAUGGGUCCUCCCCAAGAGCUUUUGGAAAAAGCCAACCCUGAGGACCCCUUGAUUUGGGGUUUCUGGCCUCCAGGCUGCAGAAGGAACCCGUUCUGGACACUUGGCCCUCUCUUGGGGGUCAUCUGCUACAGAAGCCCCAGGAAGCUGAUGCCGCUGCCCCUGGACCACCCGAGUUGCCGGCUCCCUCCCGCAGGAGGCCCCAGGCUGCCCACACGUGCCGCAGACUCCCCGUCCCUCCAGCCAGACGGCCUGCACUCAGUGCUGCGUUGAGAACACCACCGCUUGGCCGAGUCUAAGACCCAGCCUAAACCACCCAGGGUGGUGGCCACGCCUGUCUCCAGGAGGAUACAGCCCAGCAGGGCCUGCUGGGGACAGGGAUGGGUGGCUCGGCCAAGCCUUCCAGCCUGGCCUCCAGAACCCACCUACCCUACGGGGUGUGCAGCCGUCGGUGACCGAAUUCCCAGAGCCCUUCCUCUCUCAGGCCAGGGUACCACCGGGGACGAGAACAUUCAGCACUGAGCUGCAAAGGCGGGUUCUGUGGGGCCAGCCCCCGUUUGCGGGUUCUGUGGGGCCAGCCCAGUCUGCAGGUUUGUGGGUUCUGUGGGGCCAGCCCGGUUUGCAGGUUUUCAGGUUCUGUGGGGCCAGCCUGGUUUGCAGGUUUGCGGGUGGGGCUGCUCUAACAGCUUGCCCCGGAGAGGCAGCAGCAAGACAGACGGCCCCACAAGAGUGCCCCCAGCUUUUGAGCAGCCCAGGAAAACGGCACAGUAGCCUCGCCCUGGGGAGAAGCACAGCCCCAGGUGUGGGAUUGUUUACCAGCGGAAAAGGGGCCACCCACACCUCGGCAGGGAUGUGAACCUCCACGGCCUCAGAGGAAAAACAUCCAGUGUCCCCAUUCCAUUAUGGCCCAGACAAAAUAAGCAGGUCUCCAAGGAAACGGGUCCUCCUGCUGUGCCCCGGCUUAGAGGGUGAGCACGCGGCGCCACCCCGGCCGGCUGCCUGCCCGUGCCAAGGAAUUCCACAGACAGAAAGGAAGGUAUGGGUCCCCCUCCUCCAGGCACCCCCAAACCUAGCACACAACAGACAGGACAGGCUGCCUGUGUCAGGACAACUACAGCCUGCAGCUCUGGCUUCCCACACGACAAAGGACAGGGACGCUGGGCCCACCCACUGUGCCCAGCCACCGCCAACCCACUCCCCAGUGGCUCCCGAAGCCCCAGUACUGAACCUCUGGCCUGCCGCAGGGAGGGCCUGGGGGCAGAUGGGACCCCGACAGGUGUCCUAGCUCUCCCGGGAACCACCCCCCACCCCACCCCCCGCACCAGCUCACAGCUGGCAUAGGCAGCGGCCCUGCCCAUCCAUACUGGCUCUCCAAUCCCAGAGGGGCCAAGGCCCUUUGGACUCUGGCUAUGGCCCCUGCCAGCCCCAGGGGCCGAGACUCCGGGCCAGCUCUGCCGCACGUGCCUCCUGCAGCUGGCUGUGUACGCCCCCAGUCCGUGGAGCCUGAGCCUCACUGCCCUGUUCCCCUUUCAAGGGUCAGAUGUCGUCUCCUCAAAGGCCCCAACAGGGCUGGCUCCUGCCACAAGACCUACUGGGUUUGCUCCCAGCGCCCAGCGCAGAAGGUGGCAGAACGUGGCACCCAGAUGGGCUUGCGCCCGUGCCCCAGCUGGCCUUUGCAGGAUGAGGUCCCAGGCGGCCAGUGUGGCCCGUGUCCUUGCCUGCGUUUCCUCCACCCAGACACAUCCAGGCUCCACCAGAGCCCCCACCAGUGUGAGCCAAGUGCAGUCCCUCAGUCCUCUCAGCCCCAAACCAGGCCCACAGGAGGUCCCUCUGCCCGCCUUCAGCCCGGCCAAUGAGCAGCUGCCCCUCCAGAGAGAAGAGAGGAGGCGUCACACCCUCCGCGGGGACUGCAGGUCCACAGGGCAACCUGGCGCAUCUGCACCCAACAUGGGAGAAAGUGGAGGGGGUUGCUGGAACAACCUGCUCCUGCACAGCCCCGGCGGGCACCUCAGACUCUCUGGGCAGGGCUGGGUGCCUUCCUGCUCCGAUUUCCCUCACUCCCCUGGCUGAGUGAGGACAGCUCUCAGGCCUUCACAGGCCCAGAGGACUCAGGCCAUCCCCACCCACGGCCUGGCCACCUCACUGGGGACAUUAGGGCAGCUCUGGGCGGCCCACAGGCGGGGUGGCUGGCAUGUCCACCAGGAAUUCUUGGUCCAAGAAUAUGUUUCUGCGGUGCUUAUGCGGGAGCUCACACUCCCCACUGCUAAAUGCGUUUGUUCUUUGUUUUUUCCUUUCCAUGAAAUCUGGAUAUGAGCGGCUCUGAGGCUCUGUGGCCUCAGGCCCCUCCUCGCAUCCCUGAACUCUCUCCCUCCAGUGAGGAAGAGCAGAGGUAGCCGAGGCCCCUCCUCGACACUCCACACUGAGGUUCCUGCGGGCAGAGGACCUUGGACAUCGAGCGUGGGGAGACUCCGUCCACCUGCCGGCGCAUUCUGGAAAUGCCAGCAGGCCAGCCUGCAAGUGGGGUCGGCCGGCCCGAAGCCAGCAGUUCUCAGGGGAAGUGGGGGGUGCUGCUGCUGCCCAGUGACCCCACACAUCCGUACUUACAGUACCCACACCUGGUCCCGCCUUCAAAGAUGAAUCCGCUUGGCACGGCCCCGUAGCGCCGGAGGUCAGACAGCUUCCACUGCCCCGUGACAGCCGGGGGGAUGUCCCUGGCCAAGACGAGGACAUCAUUGCAGAGGUGCAGGGUAGCCGGGCCGCUCUCCAACUUGGUGCCUGGAGCCACUGUCACAUGGAACCUAUGCACUGCGGGCAGGCGGGGCAAGAGGGCAUCACGGGCGGGCAGGCUGUGUGGCUCCAUCACAGAAGGGGAAACCGAGGCUCAGGGAUCCCCCAGCCUCCAGUUCGGGUGUGGAGAGUCUGGAGUCUGUAUCGAGGCCCCAGCCUGGCCACGGGAACCUCAGGGCACCACCGGCCCUCUCUCCAUCCAGGUCAGCACACCAGGCAGACAGCAGCCUCCCCACCAGGGGCCCCACCUGCUCCAUCUCCAACCCCCAGAGCCAAAGGGACCCCUGUUCCCAUCCCACCUCCCCCUUCUCUGCCUCCUCUACCUGCUCCAAGCUGUGGCCUCAGGCGCAUCCUUGUCAGGCCACGUUCUAUCAAGAUGAAGCUGCCUGGGCGGUGCCCAGCGGCCUCUGUGCCAUGGCCCUGCGCCAGCGGAUGAAGGAAGCAGACCCAUGCCGCUGAGCCAGGCUGGAGGGAACCCCCAACGGGAGAACUUUCUGGAAAGAUGCAGUUCUUCCCUCCUAAUGUCUCCUUCCCCUGCGCCCUCCUGCAGAGCCAACCGCACCUCCUCCCACUAAGCCCCCAGCUUCUCUCUCCCCACUCAAUGGAGCAGGAGGGGCUGCUGCCUUGGGGACAAGACUGGGGGAGCGGGACACUCACCUCCAAGGCCAAAGAACUCAGCCAUCAAGGGCCAGGAUAUUUUAAUCAAUAUUUUAAAAAGUAAAGUUAUGCAGAGUCCAUGCUGAUCAAAA